CUCUUUCCGCCCGCUCCAUGGCGGUGGAUGCCUGACUGGAAGCCCGAGUGGGAUGCGGCUGACGCGGAAGCGGCUCUGCUCGUUUCUUAUCGCCCUGUACUGCCUAUUCUCCCUCUACGCUGCCUACCACGUCUUCUUCGGGCGCCGCCGCCAGGCGCCGGCCGGGUCCCCGCGGGGCCUCAGGAAGGGGGCGGCCCCCGCGCGGGAGAGACGCGGCCGAGGUAGGACUGGGUCGGCGGCUUCCUUCCGGCUCUGCGCUCCUGGCUGGGGCUGCUGGGCGGCUGGGGCCGGGUCCCCGCACCCGGCUCUCAAGUCCGGGAUUACCCGCAGGGCCUGAGAAGCGCUUUGCCCCCUACAGCCUCUCGAGCCAGCCCUUGGCUCGGAAUUGGAGAAUGGUCCUCAUUCUUACCCAGAUCUCACACGCCGUCCCCGCUCCCGAUCCCAGGGGGUGACAGGCGCGCACGCCUUUCAAACACGUGUUAAAAUCCAAGACGUCGUCUCAAAUGCCAGAGAUUUGCGGGAAUGCUCCUGGAAGGCCUCAAAAUCGCCGCAAGAACAGUCCACUUUGGAAAGUGAAGAAUGGAAUCCUUGGGAAGGAGAUGAAAAAAAUGAGCAACAACACAGAUUUAAAACUAGCCUUCAAAUAUUAGAUAAAUCCACGAAAGGAAAAACAGAUCUCAGUGUACAAAUCUGGGGCAAAGCUGCCAUUGGCUUGUAUCUCUGGGAGCAUAUUUUUGAAGGCUUACUUGAUCCCAGCGAUGUGACUGCUCAAUGGAGAGAAGGAAAGUCAAUCGUAGGAAGAACACAGUACAGCUUCAUCACUGGUCCAGCUGUAAUACCAGGGUACUUCUCCGUUGAUGUGAAUAAUGUGGUACUCAUUUUAAAUGGAAGAGAAAAAGCAAAGAUCUUUUAUGCCACCCAGUGGUUACUUUAUGCACAAAAUUUAGUGCAAAUUCAAAAACUCCAGCAUCUUGCUGUUGUUUUGCUCGGAAAUGAACAUUGUGAUAAUGAGUGGAUAAACCCAUUCCUCAAAAGAAAUGGAGGCUUCGUGGAGCUGCUUUUCAUAAUAUAUGACAGCCCCUGGAUUAAUGACGUGGAUGUUUUUCAGUGGCCUUUAGGAGUAGCAACAUACAGGAAUUUUCCUGUGGUGGAGGCAAGUUGGUCAAUGCUGCAUGAUGAGAGGCCAUAUUUAUGUAAUUUCUUAGGAACGAUUUAUGAAAAUUCAUCCAGACAGGCACUAAUGAACAUUUUGAAAAAAGAUGGGAACGAUAAGCUUUGUUGGGUUUCAGCAAGAGAACACUGGCAGCCUCAGGAAACAAAUGAAAGUCUUAAGAAUUACCAAGAUGCCUUGCUUCAGAGUGAUCUCACAUUGUGCCCGGUCGGAGUAAACACAGAAUGCUAUCGAAUCUAUGAGGCUUGCUCCUAUGGCUCCAUUCCUGUGGUGGAAGACGUGAUGACAGCUGGCAACUGUGGGAAUACAUCUGUGCACCACGGUGCUCCUCUGCAGUUACUCAAGUCCAUGGGUGCUCCCUUUAUCUUUAUCAAGAACUGGAAGGAACUCCCUGCUGUUUUAGAAAAAGAGAAAACUAUAAUUUUACAAGAAAAAAUUGAAAGAAGAAAAAUGUUACUUCAGUGGUAUCAGCACUUCAAGACAGAGCUUAAAAUGAAAUUUACUAAUAUUUUAGAAAGCUCAUUUUUAAUGAAUAAUAAAAGUUAAUUAUCUUUUUGAGCUAACAUGUGAUUUUUAAAAUCAUUUUGACUACUGGGUGUAUAAAUGUGUUUGUGUGUGUAUGUAUUUAUAGAUGUUCUUUAAGGUACCCUUGAAAACUCUACAUUAUGUAUGCCACAUAAUGACAUUUCAGUCAGUGGUAGACUACAUAUAUGAUAGUGGUCCCAUAAGAUUAUAAUGGAGCUGAAAAAUUUCUAUCGCCUAGUGAUGUCAUAGCCUAGUGAUGACAUAUGUAUUGCAAUACAUCACUCACGUGUUUGUGGUGAUACUGGUGUAAACAAAUCUAUUGCACUGCCAGUCAAGUAAAAGUACAGCAAUUAUGUCCUGUACAUAAUAUUUAAUAAUGACAAUAAAUGACUAUGUUACUGGUUUAUGUAUUUACUAUACUAUACUUUUUACAAUUUGUAUUAGUUCUUGCAUUGCUAUGAAUAAAUGCCUGAGAUUGAGUAAUUUAUAAA